AAACGGGGCCCAAGGCAGGGGUGGCGGGUCAGUGCUGCUCGGGGGCUUCUCCAUCCAGGUCCCUGGAGUUCCUGGUCCCUGGAGCUCCGCACUUGGCGGCGCAACCUGCGUGAGGCAGCGCGACUCUGGCGACUGGCCGGCCAUGCCUUCCCGGGCUGAGGACUAUGAAGUGUUGUACACCAUUGGCACAGGCUCCUACGGCCGCUGCCAGAAGAUCCGGAGGAAGAGUGAUGGCAAGAUAUUAGUUUGGAAAGAACUUGACUAUGGCUCCAUGACAGAAGCUGAGAAACAGAUGCUUGUUUCUGAAGUGAAUUUGCUUCGUGAACUGAAACAUCCAAACAUCGUUCGUUACUAUGAUCGGAUUAUUGACCGGACCAAUACAACACUGUACAUUGUAAUGGAAUAUUGUGAAGGAGGGGAUCUGGCUAGUGUAAUUACAAAGGGAACCAAGGAAAGGCAAUACUUAGAUGAAGAGUUUGUUCUUCGAGUGAUGACUCAGUUGACUCUGGCCCUGAAGGAAUGCCACAGACGAAGUGAUGGUGGUCAUACCGUAUUGCAUCGGGAUCUGAAACCAGCCAAUGUUUUCCUGGAUGGCAAGCAAAACGUCAAGCUUGGAGACUUUGGGCUAGCUAGAAUAUUAAACCAUGACACGAGUUUUGCAAAAACAUUUGUUGGCACACCUUAUUACAUGUCUCCUGAACAAAUGAAUCGCAUGUCCUACAAUGAGAAAUCAGAUAUCUGGUCAUUGGGCUGCUUGCUGUAUGAGUUAUGUGCAUUAAUGCCUCCAUUUACAGCUUUUAGCCAGAAAGAACUCGCUGGGAAAAUCAGAGAAGGCAAAUUCAGGCGAAUUCCAUACCGUUACUCUGAUGAAUUGAAUGAAAUUAUUACGAGGAUGUUAAACUUAAAGGAUUACCAUCGACCUUCUGUUGAAGAAAUUCUUGAGAACCCUUUAAUAGCAGAUUUGGUUGCAGACGAGCAAAGAAGAAAUCUUGAGAGAAGAGGGCGACAAUUAGGAGAGCCAGAAAAAUCGCAGGAUUCCAGCCCUGUAUUGAGUGAGCUGAAACUGAAGGAAAUUCAGUUACAGGAGCGAGAGCGAGCUCUCAAAGCAAGAGAAGAAAGAUUGGAGCAGAAAGAACAGGAGCUUUGUGUUCGUGAGAGACUAGCAGAGGACAAACUGGCUAGAGCAGAAAAUCUGUUGAAGAACUACAGCUUGCUAAAGGAACGGAAGUUCCUGUCUCUGGCAAGUAAUCCAGAACUUCUUAAUCUUCCAUCCUCAGUAAUUAAGAAGAAAGUUCAUUUCAGUGGGGAAAGUAAAGAGAACAUCAUGAGGAGUGAGAAUUCUGAGAGUCAGCUCACAUCUAAGUCCAAGUGCAAGGACCUGAAGAAAAGGCUUCACGCUGCCCAGCUGCGGGCUCAAGCCCUGUCAGAUAUUGAGAAAAAUUACCAACUGAAAAGCAGACAGAUCCUGGGCAUGCGCUAGCCAGGUAGAGAGACACAGAGCUGUGUACAGGAUGUAAUAUUACCAACCUUUAAAGACUGAUAUUCAAAUGCUGUAGUGUUGAAUACUUGGUUCCAUGAGCCAUGCCUUUCUGUAUAGUACACAUGAUAUUUCGGAAUUGGUUUUACUGUUCUUCAGCAACUAUUGUACAAAAUGUUCACAUUUAAUUUUUCUUUCUUCUUUUAAGAACAUAUUAUAAAAAGAAUACUUUCUUGGUUGGGCUUUUAAUCCUGUGUGUGAUUACUAGUAGGAACAUGAGAUGUGACAUUCUAAAUCUUGGGAGAAAAAAUAAUGUUAGGAAAAAAAUAUUUAUGCAGGAAGAGUAGCACUCACUGAAUAGUUUUAAAUGACUGAGUGGUAUGCUUACAAUUGUCAUGUCUAGAUUUAAAUUUUAAGUCUGAGAUUUUAAAUGUUUUUGAGCUUAGAAAACCCAGUUAGAUGCAAUUUGGUCAUUAAUACCAUGACAUCUUGCUUAUAAAUAUUCCAUUGCUCUGUAGUUCAAAUCUGUUAGCUUUGUGAAAAUUCAUCACUGUGAUGUUUGUAUUCUUUUUUUUUUUCUGUUUAACAGAAUAUGAGCUGUCUGUCAUUUACCUACUUCUUUCCCACUAAAUAAAAGAAUUCUUCAGUUUCCCUGUA